CCUAAAGCGAGGAAACCAAGCCGGGCGCCUCUUGCAAUGGAGACGGUGAGGAGUGCAGGAGGGCGGUCGGGGGCGCUGUGGAGCCUAAGACACCCCCCCAACCCUUAGGAGACCGGGAGGGCCGGGCAGGGGCUGGCGCUGGUGUCUAGCAAACAAAAAGCAGCCGGGUGUCUGCCCUAUCCCGUGACCCUGUUCCUCCGCUUCUUCGUUGGGCGCAUCUCCUGGAACUGGGCCGCGUCCCCGCCGCCUUUCCGUACGCGGUACCCUUAGCCCAAGCAGGCAGUGACUCCUGGCUCCCUCCUUGGGGCCCACGUAUGCCGUGGCAAUCUCGGGCCUCCUUUCCUAUUGGCACCUCAAGCCCUUUUAGAGGUUUGAGAGCGCAGGGUUGUGAGCCGGCUUUGCUGGGUGAGGCACGGGGCGUCCAGAGGGAUCUCCGCUUGCAGGUAGCUCCUGGACCUCGAUGGUCUUUCUGUGAUCCCUGCAAUCCCCGGCAGGAGGACAUCUGAAGAUCUUUAUACUGCGUCCAGUGAAGUCACAUUCCCUUAAUAAGACCGAGAAUUGAGGUUUGCUUGAAAGAGGAAAUCUUGCAGUGUUAGAGGCCGAUGUGUCCCUGGACAAUUUUAGGUCAUGGCCCGCUCUGCGACUCUAAGCAGGGGUUUUGGCAUAGCUCAUUCUUGGCGAGCAGGCAUUGACCAAUUGUGGCAGGGCCCUGUCACCCUCCCACAGAUGCUGCGGGUUGCCUGCUACAUGUUUGCACCCACCCUCACUCUCAGGAGUCUUUUUCUAGCGCUCUGUAACCCCUCCCAUACACUUCCCUCUCCACAGUUUUUAACCAUGUGUCUUCUUUCAGGCAGAGUAACUCUUUCCAUCUUGGUUUUUAUCAUCUGCUACUGUAGUUACGAAAGGACUGCAGGUUCACUUUGCUUUGGAUUACAUGCCCAGAGUAAUUCUUUGCCACACCGUUUCUCUGCUCACAGAGAGGUUGUUUCUUUCAGGUUUUCAAAAAGAAAACCGACCAAAGUACUAAAAUGAUUCGCAGUUGGUCUCCCAGGCAAGGGAGCCAAUUCUGACUAAUCAGGAUAAUCUUAAACAAAAAUAAGGAGUCUAAUUCCAUUAAAUUUAAAAUGACAUGUCAUAUUCUACUUACUUGUAAAUGUAUUAUGGUUUACAAAGCAUUUUUAUAUAGAUUUUCUAAUUUAGCCUUUACACUUUAUGUACUGGAUUAGGCUCUGGGGUAGAAGUUAAAAAGAGGAAAAAGAAAACUCAGCCAGGUGUGGUGGCUCACGCCUGUAAUGCCAGUACUUUGGGAGGCCAAGGCAAGUGGAUUGCUUGAGCUCAGGAGUUCAGCAUCAGCCUGGGCAACAUGAUGAAAGCCUGUCUCGACAGAAACAAAAAUACAAAAAUUACCCAGGCGUGGUGGUGGUGGUGUGUGCCUGUAGUCCCAGCUACUCGGGAGGCUCAGGUGGGAGGAUCGCUUGAUCCAAAGAGGUGGAGGCUGGAGUGAGCUGAGAUCAUGCCACUGCACUCCAGUCUGAGUGACACAGUGAGAUCCUGUCUCCAAAAAAAAAGAAAAGAAAGAAAACUCCUGCUUUGAAAAUGUUCAGCCUAACUGGAGUGAUGGUGAGGGCAAGCCAGCAACAGCUGUUAUUUAAAGGUAGACUAUAAUAAAUGCUGUCAUCAAUAUGAAAACAGAGGACUGUGACAGAAUAGCUGAGAGAAAAAUUACUUUGGACCUAGGAGAGGGCACUGCAAAUUGAGAGAACAGUGUGAGCAAGGGCACUGAAAUUGGGGUAUGUAGAGAACUGGGGGUGAGCCAGCGGCAUGAUGUUGCUGGCUUUGGAUUUUGGUCACAGUGGGAGAAAAGACUGGAAAAGCAGGCUAAGAUCAGGUUGAAGGUAUUACACACCAUGCUAAAUUUGAACUUUGUUUUGUAAUAGGGGACCCAUGGAAGAUUUAUGAGCAAGUCAGUGAAUGUCCUUUAGGAAUGUUCAUAGCAGCUUUCUGUACAUGGACUGAGCUACUUCGAAAAGUAAAGUUUCUUGUUAAUGGGGAUGAAAGUCCCUUCCAAAUCUGAGAUGCUUUGGUGAACAAACUUGGUGAAAGCAUGAAAGAUAAAUUGAAGAACAGAUAGAUUUGGGCCAAGGACCCCAGUUUAAACAACGUUGCAGAGGUCAUUUCUUCAGAUAGCUCCCCAGCUGUGGAAAAUGAGCAUCCUCAAGGUGAAGAAAGCUUUUUUUGCUUUGGUGACUAACGGUGUACGAGCUGCCCCUUUAUGGGAUAGUAAGAAGCAAAGUUUUGUGGGCAUGCUGACCAUCACUGAUUUCAUCAAUAUCCUGCACCGCUACUAUAAAUCAGCCUUGGUACAGAUCUAUGAGCUAGAAGAACACAAGAUAGAAACUUGGAGAGAGGUGUAUCUCCAGGACUCCUUUAAACCGCUUGUCUGCAUUUCUCCUAAUGCCAGCUUGUUUGAUGCUGUCUCUUCAUUAAUUCGGAACAAGAUCCACAGGCUGCCAGUUAUUGACCCAGAAUCAGGCAAUACUUUGUACAUCCUCACCCACAAGCGCAUUCUGAAGUUCCUCAAAUUGUUUAUCACUGAGUUCCCCAAGCCAGAGUUCAUGUCCAAGUCUCUGGAAGAGCUACAGAUUGGCACCUAUGCCAAUAUUGCUAUGGUUCGCACUACCACCCCCGUCUAUGUGGCUCUGGGGAUUUUUGUACAGCAUCGAGUCUCAGCCCUGCCAGUGGUGGAUGAGAAGGGGCGUGUGGUGGACAUCUACUCCAAGUUUGAUGUUAUCAAUCUGGCAGCAGAAAAGACCUACAACAACCUAGAUGUAUCUGUGACUAAAGCCUUGCAACAUCGAUCACAUUACUUUGAGGGUGUUCUCAAGUGCUACCUGCAUGAGACUCUGGAGACCAUCAUCAACAGGCUAGUGGAAGCAGAGGUUCACCGACUUGUAGUGGUGGAUGAAAAUGAUGUGGUCAAGGGAAUUGUAUCACUGUCUGACAUCCUGCAGGCCCUGGUGCUCACAGGUGGAGAGAAGAAGCCCUGAGCUGGGGGAAGGGGUCAUGCAGCACCAGGGGAUAUGCCCAACUCACUGCCUGCUGGAAGCUCUGUGGGAAUCAGAUGAAACUUGAGGGAAUUGUGACUCUGUUCCCUGUUCAGGGUCCCCUGCCCUUCUAUCUGGGAGCUAGGGAAGGUAUGGGGGAGGAAAGAGAAUGGAUUUAUAGCUACCCUUACCCUCACACAUACACUUGAAAAAACUUUCAGCCUAGCCAGUUCUAGCCCCUGUCCUCUUAGAUAUAUCCCCCUUUCUGGGUGAACUAUAGGCUCUGUGCCUCUCAGACAAAUUCUGAUCUCUAAGAGAUCCCCAGACCUCACUUGCCUCUGCCUCCAUCUUGGCCCUGAUUCAACCCUAAGAUAAUAGCACAACAAAAUUCUUCAUAAAGAUAUUUUUAUUCACCUGUUCCGUGCUAUAUGGAGGAGGCCAAGUCCAUUUAGUGACAUUUCUUCCCAUAAUGUGAGUGGGGAGGAUUGUGGGGAGGAGGGGCUUUGGGUUCCUGUGUUUGUGCAUAUGAAGGGAGAUGGGGGUUAGGUGGAGGAGGAGAGCAGCGUGGUUAGCUAAGGUUAUUGCUUUUUGUGGCAAAUCUAAUUAAAUGACAGGAAUCUCUUCACGA